AGAUGAAGUGUGGCUCUAUCUUGUAUGUGAGCACACCCACAUUUUCACUGCCAUUAUCUGGGACAGCAGAACCAGGUUUGGCUCAACAGAUUUCUCUUUCCACCCAUCUAUUGCAGGUGUAGUGGUCUUGCUGCUUCUCCAGGGAGGAUCUGCCUACAAACUGGUUUGCUACUUUACCAACUGGUCCCAGGACCGGCAGGAACCAGGAAAAUUCACCCCUGAGAAUAUUGACCCCUUCCUAUGCUCUCAUCUCAUCUAUUCAUUCGCCAGCAUCGAAAACAACAAGGUUAUCAUCAAGGACAAGAGUGAAGUGAUGCUCUACCAGACCAUCAACAGUCUCAAAACCAAGAAUCCCAAACUGAAAAUUCUCUUGUCCAUUGGAGGGUACCUGUUUGGUUCCAAAGGGUUCCACCCUAUGGUGGAUUCUUCUACAUCACGCUUGGAAUUCAUUAACUCCAUAAUCCUGUUUCUGAGGAACCAUAACUUUGAUGGACUGGAUGUAAGCUGGAUCUACCCAGAUCAGAAAGAAAACACUCAUUUCACUGUGCUGAUUCAUGAGUUAGCAGAAGCCUUUCAGAAGGACUUCACAAAAUCCACCAAGGAAAGGCUUCUCUUGACUGCGGGCGUAUCUGCAGGGAGGCAAAUGAUUGAUAACAGCUAUCAAGUUGAGAAACUGGCAAAAGAUCUGGAUUUCAUCAACCUCCUGUCCUUUGACUUCCAUGGGUCUUGGGAAAAGCCCCUUAUCACUGGCCACAACAGCCCUCUGAGCAAGGGGUGGCAGGACAGAGGGCCAAGCUCCUACUACAAUGUGGAAUAUGCUGUGGGGUACUGGAUACAUAAGGGAAUGCCAUCAGAGAAGGUGGUCAUGGGCAUCCCCACAUAUGGGCACUCCUUCACACUGGCCUCUGCAGAAACCACCGUGGGGGCCCCUGCCUCUGGCCCUGGAGCUGCUGGACCCAUCACAGAGUCUUCAGGCUUCCUGGCCUAUUAUGAGAUCUGCCAGUUCCUGAAAGGAGCCAAGAUCACGCGGCUCCAGGAUCAGCAGGUUCCCUACGCAGUCAAGGGGAACCAGUGGGUGGGCUAUGAUGAUGUGAAGAGUAUGGAGACCAAGGUUCAGUUCUUAAAGAAUUUAAACCUGGGAGGAGCCAUGAUCUGGUCUAUUGACAUGGAUGACUUCACUGGCAAAUCCUGCAACCAGGGCCCUUACCCUCUUGUCCAAGCAGUCAAGAGAAGCCUUGGCUCCCUGUGAAGGAUUAACUUACAGAGAAGCAGGCAAGAUGACCUUGCUGCCUGGGGCCUGCUCUCUCCCAGGAAUUCUCAUGUGGGAUUCCCCUUGCCAGGCUGGCCUUUGGAUCUCUCUUCCAAGCCUUUCCUGACUUCCUCUUAGAUCAUAGAUUGGACCUGGUUUUGUUUUCCUGCAGCUGUUGACUUGUUGCCCUGAAGUACAAUAAAAAAAAUUCAUUUUGCUCCAGUAA